AAACCCUCUGUAAAGUAACAGAAGUUAGAAGGGGAAAUGUCGCCUCUCUGAAGAUUACCCAAAGAAAAAGUGAUUUGUCAUUGCUUUAUAGACUGUAAGAAGAGAACAUCUCAGAAGUGGAGUCUUACCCUGAAAUCAAAGGAUUUAAAGAAAAAGUGGAAUUUUUCUUCAGCAAGCUGUGAAACUAAAUCCACAACCUUUGGAGACCCAGGAACACCCUCCAAUCUCUGUGUGUUUUGUAAACAUCACUGGAGGGUCUUCUACGUGAGCAAUUGGAUUGUCAUCAGCCCUGCCUGUUUUGCACCUGGGAAGUGCCCUGGUCUUACUUGGGUCCAAAUUGUUGGCUUUCACUUUUGACCCUAAGCAUCUGAAGCCAUGGGCCACACACGGAGGCAGGGAACAUCACCAUCCAAGUGUCCAUACCUCAAUUUCUUUCAGCUCUUGGUGCUGGCUGGUCUUUCUCACUUCUGUUCAGGUGUUAUCCACGUGACCAAGGAAGUGAAAGAAGUGGCAACGCUGUCCUGUGGUCACAAUGUUUCUGUUGAAGAGCUGGCACAAACUCGCAUCUACUGGCAAAAGGAGAAGAAAAUGGUGCUGACUAUGAUGUCUGGGGACAUGAAUAUAUGGCCCGAGUACAAGAACCGGACCAUCUUUGAUAUCACUAAUAACCUCUCCAUUGUGAUCCUGGCUCUGCGCCCAUCUGACGAGGGCACAUACGAGUGUGUUGUUCUGAAGUAUGAAAAAGACGCUUUCAAGCGGGAACACCUGGCUGAAGUGACGUUAUCAGUCAAAGCUGACUUCCCUACACCUAGUAUAUCUGACUUUGAAAUUCCAACUUCUAAUAUUAGAAGGAUAAUUUGCUCAACCUCUGGAGGUUUUCCAGAGCCUCACCUCUCCUGGUUGGAAAAUGGAGAAGAAUUAAAUGCCAUCAACACAACAGUUUCCCAAGAUCCUGAAACUGAGCUCUAUGCUGUUAGCAGCAAACUGGAUUUCAAUAUGACAACCAACCACAGCUUCAUGUGUCUCAUCAAGUAUGGACAUUUAAGAGUGAAUCAGACCUUCAACUGGAAUACAACCAAGCAAGAGCAUUUUCCUGAUAACCUGCUCCCAUCCUGGGCCAUUACCUUAAUCUCAGUAAAUGGAAUUUUUGUGAUAUGCUGCCUGACCUACUGCUUUGCCCCAAGAUGCAGAGAGAGAAGGAGGAAUGAGAGAUUGAGAAGGGAAAGUGUACGCCCUGUAUAACAGUGUCCGCAGAAGCAAGGGGCUGAAAAGAUCUGAAGGUCCCACCUCCAUUUGCAAUUGACCUCUUCUGGGAACUUCCUCAGAUGGACAAGAUUACCCCACCUUGCCCUUUACGUAUCUGCUCUUAGGUGCUUCUUCACUUCAGUUGCUUUGCAGGAAGUGUCUAGAGGAAUAUGGUGGGCACAGAAGUAGCUCUGGUGACCUUGAUCAAGGUGUUUUGAAAUGCAGAAUUCUUGAGUUCUGGAAGGGACUUUAGAGAAUACCAGUGUUAUUAAUGACAAAGGCACUGAGGCCCAGGGAGGUGACCCGAAUUAUAAAGGCCAGCGCCAGAACCCAGAUUUCCUAACUCUGGUGCUCUUUCCCUUUAUCAGUUUGACUGUGGCCUGUUAACUGGUAUAUACAUAUAUAUGUCAGGCAAAGUGCUGCUGGAAGUAGAAUUUGUCCAAUAACAGGUCAACUUCAGAGACUAUCUGAUUUCCUAAUGUCAGAGUAGAAGAUUUUAUGCUGCUGUUUACAAAAGCCCAAUGUAAUGCAUAGGAAGUAUGGCAUGAACAUCUUUAGGAGACUAAUGGAAAUAUUAUUGGUGUUUACCCAGUAUUCCAUUUUUUUCAUUGUGUUCUCUAUUGCUGCUCUCUCACUCCCCCAUGAGGUACAGCAGAAAGGAGAACUAUCCAAAACUAAUUUCCUCUGACAUGUAAGACGAAUGAUUUAGGUACGUCAAAGCAGUAGUCAAGGAGGAAAGGGAUAGUCCAAAGACUUAACUGGUUCAUAUUGGACUGAUAAUCUCUUUAAAUGGCUUUAUGCUAGUUUGACCUCAUUUGUAAAAUAUUUAUGAGAAAGUUCUCAUUUAAAAUGAGAUCGUUGUUUACAGUGUAUGUACUAAGCAGUAAGCUAUCUUCAAAUGUCUAAGGUAGUAACUUUCCAUAGGGCCUCCUUAGAUCCCUAAGAUGGCUUUUUCUCCUUGGUAUUUCUGGGUCUUUCUGACAUCAGCAGAGAACUGGAAAGACAUAGCCAACUGCUGUUCAUGUUACUCAUGACUCCUUUCUCUAAAACUGCCUUCCACAAUUCACUAGACCAGAAGUGGACGCAACUUAAGCUGGGAUAAUCACAUUAUCAUCUGAAAAUCUGGAGUUGAACAGCAAAAGAAGACAACAUUUCUCAAAUGCACAUCUCAUGGCAGCUAAGCCACAUGGCUGGGAUUUAAAGCCUUUAGAGCCAGCCCAUGGCUUUAGCUACCUCACUAUGCUGCUUCACAAACCUUGCUCCUGUGUAAAACUAUAUUCUCAGUGUAGGGCAGAGAGGUCUAACACCAACAUAAGGUACUAGCAGUGUUUCCCGUAUUGACAGGAAUACUUAACUCAAUAAUUCUUUUCUUUUCCAUUUAGUAACAGUUGUGAUGACUAUGUUUCUAUUCUAAGUAAUUCCUGUAUUCUACAGCAGAUACUUUGUCAGCAAUACUAAGGGAAGAAACAAAGUUGAACCGUUUCUUUAAUAA